GUGGAGAGAGCGCGGAGACAAGCGCAGAGCGCAGCGCACGGCCACAGACAGCCCUGGGCAUCCACCGACGGCGCAGCCGGAGCCAGCAGAGCCGGAAGGCGCGCCCCGGGCAGAGAAAGCCGAGCAGAGCUGGGUGGCGUCUCCGGGCCGCCGCUCCGACGGGCCAGCGCCCUCCCCAUGUCCCUGCUCCCACGCCGCGCCCCUCCGGUCAGCAUGAGGCUCCUGGCGGCCGCGCUGCUCCUGCUGCUGCUGGCGCUGUACACCGCGCGUGUGGACGGGUCCAAAUGCAAGUGCUCCCGGAAGGGACCCAAGAUCCGCUACAGCGACGUGAAGAAGCUGGAAAUGAAGCCAAAGUACCCGCACUGCGAGGAGAAGAUGGUUAUCAUCACCACCAAGAGCGUGUCCAGGUACCGAGGUCAGGAGCACUGCCUGCACCCCAAGCUGCAGAGCACCAAGCGCUUCAUCAAGUGGUACAACGCCUGGAACGAGAAGCGCAGGGUCUACGAAGAAUAGGGUGAAAAACCUCAGAAGGGAAAACUCCAAACCAGUUGGGAGACUUGUGCAAAGGACUUUGCAGAUUAAAAAAAAAAAAAAAAAAAAAAAAAAAAAAAAAAAAAAAAAAAGCCUUUCUUUCUCACAGGCAUAAGACACAAAUUAUAUAUUGUUAUGAAGCACUUUUUACCAACGGUCAGUUUUUACAUUUUAUAGCUGCGUGCGAAAGGCUUCCAGAUGGGAGACCCAUCUCUCUUGUGCUCCAGACUUCAUCACAGGCUGCUUUUUAUCAAAAAGGGGAAAACUCAUGCCUUUCCUUUUUAAAAAAUGCUUUUUUGUAUUUGUCCAUACGUCACUAUACAUCUGAGCUUUAUAAGCGCCCGGGAGGAACAAUGAGCUUGGUGGACACAUUUCAUUGCAGUGUUGCUCCAUUCCUAGCUUGGGAAGCUUCCGCUUAGAGGUCCUGGCGCCUCGGCACAGCUGCCACGGGCUCUCCUGGGCUUAUGGCCGGUCACAGCCUCAGUGUGACUCCACAGUGGCCCCUGUAGCCGGGCAAGCAGGAGCAGGUCUCUCUGCAUCUGUUCUCUGAGGAACUCAAGUUUGGUUGCCAGAAAAAUGUGCUUCAUUCCCCCCUGGUUAAUUUUUACACACCCUAGGAAACAUUUCCAAGAUCCUGUGAUGGCGAGACAAAUGAUCCUUAAAGAAGGUGUGGGGUCUUUCCCAACCUGAGGAUUUCUGAAAGGUUCACAGGUUCAAUAUUUAAUGCUUCAGAAGCAUGUGAGGUUCCCAACACUGUCAGCAAAAACCUUAGGAGAAAACUUAAAAAUAUAUGAAUACAUGCGCAAUACACAGCUACAGACACACAUUCUGUUGACAAGGGAAAACCUUCAAAGCAUGUUUCUUUCCCUCACCACAACAGAACAUGCAGUACUAAAGCAAUAUAUUUGUGAUUCCCCAUGUAAUUCUUCAAUGUUAAACAGUGCAGUCCUCUUUCGAAAGCUAAGAUGACCAUGCGCCCUUUCCUCUGUACAUAUACCCUUAAGAACGCCCCCUCCACACACUGCCCCCCAGUAUAUGCCGCAUUGUACUGCUGUGUUAUAUGCUAUGUACAUGUCAGAAACCAUUAGCAUUGCAUGCAGGUUUCAUAUUCUUUCUAAGAUGGAAAGUAAUAAAAUAUAUUUGAAAUGUACCAAAA